GUAGAAGUAUUGCGCCGUUGGUGAUUACGGAAGAACCAGGAGUUUGGCGUGACCAUGGUGAGAGAAGACGGUCCAAGAAGGGACGUUAUCAGGCCACUUUUUGGGUGGAGAAGGAGGGGAAGCAAAAGAAAACAAGGAAGUAUGCGACCAUGAAGCGAAUGCUUAGUCUCAGAGAUCAGAGGCUUAAAGAAAAGGAUAGAUUAAAACCUAAAAAGAAAGAAAAGAAGGAUCCCAGCGCAUUAAAGGAAAGAGAAGUUCCCCAACACCCUUCCUGCUUAUUUUUCCAAUAUAAUACACAGCUGGGCCCACCUUACCACAUCCUCGUUGAUACCAACUUUAUCAACUUUUCCAUAAAAGCCAAACUGGACUUAGUGCAGUCAAUGAUGGACUGUCUGUAUGCCAAGUGUAUCCCAUGUAUAACCGAUUGUGUAAUGGCUGAAAUUGAGAAAUUGGGGCAGAAGUAUCGAGUGGCUCUAAGGAUUGCCAAGGAUCCAAGAUUUGAACGAUUACCAUGUACACACAAAGGAACCUAUGCAGAUGACUGCUUAGUACAGAGAGUAACUCAGCAUAAGUGUUACAUUGUGGCCACAGUUGACCGGGACCUGAAAAGAAGAAUCCGUAAGAUUCCUGGAGUUCCUAUCAUGUACAUUUCUAACCAUAGAUACAACAUUGAACGGAUGCCAGAUGAUUAUGGAGCCCCUCGAUUCUAAUUCUUACAAGACACAGUUCCUCUGCCUUUCUUCGACCAACUUUCUCUUGUUGCCAGUUCAUUACACAAAAUGUAGCGGGAUUUUUAAGGAAUCAGAGAGACUGAUGGAGUUCAGGGAGAUAUUUAUUAUUUAGGUGCACCAGCCCAGUCAGAUUAACAUCCAAAGGACUGAACCCUGAACAGAGUUAAGUUACCUUUUAAGCAUUUUGUGGGGCCGCGGGGGUUGGGGGGAAUCUGUGCAGGGGGAAGCAUAUUACAGAAGCAAGAAAGACAGUUAUUCAAUUAACUGAGACAUGCAUUACAUCAUUUCUUACUUUUCAAGGAAAAUCAUGUUUUACGACUUGAGUUUAUCUGUCUAGUUACCUUGCAGCUGCACAGCUAGAGAAACAGGGUAUUUACAAUGCCUGGGAAAGGAGGAGAGAUAAGGCUCACUAGCCACAGAAAAACAGGCAGUUAAUUUUUAAAGGACUCCAGCUCUUUCUCUUUCUCACGGGGAAUUGGAUUUUCUUACAUGCAACUGAAUUUCUGCUUACACAUUUUUAAAUUUCUUUUAAUUGCUUUUCCAAUGCAAUAGCAUGAAUUAUUAUUCUGUUGACCUAUUUGCCUUACUAUGAGCUGAGGGUAGUUCAAUAUGCUCACUCUUUUUUUUUUUUUUCUUGAGAUGAAGUUUUGCUCUGUCACCAGGCUGGAGUGCAGUGGCGUGAUCUGGGCUCACUGCAACCCCUGCCUCCCAUCCUUCAAGUGAUUCUCCUGCCUCAGCCUCCCGAGUAGCUGGGAUUACAGGUACACACCACCAUGCUCAACUAAUUUUUCUUUUUUGGGCGGGGGGGGUGGAUAUUUUUAGUAGAGACAAAUACUUUUGUAUUUUUAAUACAGAAAAGUAUGCCUCGGCCUCCCAAAGUGCUGGAAUUACAGACAUGAGCCACUGUGCCUGGCCUGCUCACUUUCUGAUGCUGCUUUUUUGUUGUUUGUUUGUUUAUUUGUUUGUUUUGAGACGGAGUCUCGCUCUGUCACCAGGCUGGAGUGCAGUGGCGCAAUCUCGGCUCAUUGCAACCUCCGCCUCCCAGGUUCAAGCGAUUCUCCUGCCUCAGCCUGCGGAGUAGCUGGGACUAUAGGUGCGUGCCACCACGUCCAGCCACUGAUGCUGUUUUGCCACUGAUGCUGUUUUGAAAUUGAUAUUUUGUCUCAUAAAAACUAGGCCAGGCAUGGUGGCUCAUUCCUGUAAUCCCAGCACUUUGGGAGGCCAAGGUGGGUGGAUCACCUGAGGUCAGGAGUUGGAGAUGAGCCUGGACAACAUGGCAAAACCCCACCUCUACUAAAAAUACAAAAAAAAUUAGCUGGGUAUGGUGUCACGUGCCUGUAAUCCCAGCCACUGGGGAGGCUGAGGCAGGAGAACCUCUUGAACCCAGGAGGUGGAGGUUGCAGUGAGCUGAGAUUGCGCCACUGCAUUCCAGCCUGGGUGACAGAGUGAGACUGUCUCAAAAAAAAAAAAAAAUUAAUGAUGGUCAAAGGGUAUAAAAUCUCAGACAGGAAGAAUAUGUUUUAUGCUUUUUUUGAGUUCUGUUGUACAGUGUGGUGCCUAUACUUAAUAAUGGGGUAUUAUACAUUUCAAAAUUGAUGUUCUCAUCACAGAAAUGUAUUUGAAGUAUUGCAUAUGUUAACUAGCUUGAUUUAACUAUUCCAUAUUGUAUCCACAAUUUAUGAUAUCACUUUGUAACCCAUACAUUUAUACAAUUAUAAAUUGUCAAUUUACAAUAAAAAAUUUUUGUUGCGUCUUUUUAGAAAUCAGAUAUUCUGAUGAUUGCUCACAUAAUUUGGCGGUCAUUGUUUUAUACUGACUUACUCAAUAAACAUUUAUUAAAUGUAUACUAGGUGCUUAAUAAGAGAUGGUCCUGCCCUCAAGACACUCAUUAUGGUGGGAAAGAAAAACAUGUAAAUGAAUAAAUGCCGUAAAAUAGCAGUGCUAGGGUAAAAGUUUCAGAGGCAUGUCAUGGGCACAUAAAGGUGGAAUGAUUUUUUUCUACUGGUUGGGAUGGAGAGGGAGGAAAGGCCAGUGGUCAUGUGGUUUGAGCUAAUCUUAAAAAUGAAUAGGUGCCUCCCCAGUAAAUUAGGAAUGGAAGAUGAAGCAUAGGAAACAGUACACCAUAGAAAAUCCAUUAACCUAUGUAUAAUCCCAGCACUUUGGGAGACUGAGGUGGGCAGAUCACUUGAGGUCAGGAGUUUGAAACCAGCCUGGCCAACAUGGUGAAACCCCACCUCUACUAAAAAUUCCAAAAUUAACUGGGCGUGGUGGUGCAAGCCUGUAGUCCCAGCUACUUGGGAGGCUGAGGCAGGAGAAUCGCUUGAACCCGGGAGGCAGAGGUUGCAACGAGCCGAGAUCACGCCACUGCACUCCAGCCUGGGCGACAGAGUGAAACUCUGUCUCAAAAACAAACAAACAAAAAACCUAUGUAUUUGUGGGGAUUUGGUAUAUUAUUAAGGUGGUAUUUCGUUUCUGUGGGAAAAGGAAAUUUCAUUAACAGGCCAAAUAGUCUGGAGUCAUUCUGUUAGUGUUAGAAUACUAAUUCCACCAGUUAAUAUCUGUAUGAGUUGGACAAACCAUAUAACCAUCUGUUGCCUUCCUUGUUUCCUCUUUAAAGUGUUUAAUCCGCAAAACAAACCUGAUAAAGUGAGAUUAAAUUGAAUAGUACCUGGCCCAAGUAAGUGUUCUUCAGUAAAUGUUAGUGAUUAUUACACAAUGGCAAGGUGGCUAUCCAUUUGAAAAAAAAUUAGGCCGGGCGUGGUGGCUCACACCUGUAAUCCCAACACUUUGGGAGGCCAAGGUGGGCGGAUCACCUGAGGUCAGGAGCCCAAGACCAGCCUGACCAACAUGGAGAAACCCCAUCUCUACUAAAAAUACAAAAAAACAAUUAGGCAGGCAUGGUGGCAAAUGCCUGUAUUCCCAGCUACUCUGGAGGCUGAGGCAGGAGAACGCUUGAACCUGGGAGAUGGAGGUUGUGAUGAGCCGAGAUCAUGCCAUUGCACUCAUUCCAGCCUGGGCAACAAGAGUGAAACUCUGUCUCAAAAAAAAAAAAAAAAAAAGAGAGAGAGAAAAAAAUUAGUUUCCUACUUCACAUGAUUCAUAAAAAUAUUUCAAGUGGAUCAAAGACCUAAAUUUUUUUUUUUUUUGAGACAGUUUCUCACUCUGUCACCCAGGCUGCAGUGCGUUGGCACAAUCAUGACUCACUGCAGCCUUGACCUUCCCAGGCCCUGAUGAUCCACCCCAGCCUCUCAAGUAGCUGGGAUUUUUGUAUUUCUUACAGAGAUGGGAUUUUGCCUUAUUGCCCACCUUGGCCUUCUAAAGUAUUGGGAUUAUGGGCAUGAGCCACUGCACCCACCCUAAACUUAUUUCUAAGCUAUGGAAGCAUUAGGAAAAUAAAUGUAAAGAAAAACGUGUUUAUCACCUUUGGAUAGAAUUCUUAAGCAGAAUCUAAAAAGAUUGAAGAGUUUGAAUAUAUUAAAAUUAUAGAUUUCUGUGCAAGACACUCCCCUCCCCUAAAAAACAAGUGACUGAUGAGAUUUUCCAAUACAUGUAACAAGGGUUUAGAGAAAUGAGUACUGAUGUCAUGCUGACAGAAGUGCAAAUAUUUAUGGCCAUUUUUUACAGCUGUUGACAAGAUCCACUAAAAUAAAAAUUGCAGAUAUCCUGUGA